GUUCGCCGGGCAGGCGAGGAAAGAGGACGCCAUGAUUGGUUGGCGCUGGGGCGGCGGACGGUGGAAGGGCCUGGCGAGUCUAGGUUUUACGCCUGUGCUGGACUUUCUCCUUCCAUGUUUCCAGGCCGUGGGGGGCUACAGAGGGCGAGAAGUCGGCUCAGCGGAAACCUGGAUUUGGUUCUAAGCCGUGGGGUUGAGAAGGGGUGACCGGAAGUGAUCGUGGGACUGACCGGAAGCGAGGCCUGGAGGGGAAAGAGAGAGCGAGACCUGGGAGGGAGGGGGCCUCCAGCAGAAAGGGGCGGGGGAAAAGGUGCAAAAGCAGCGUGGGAGCGCCGGGCUGGCUUCCUGCGGCUGCUGCUGGUCUGACUGGGAAGCAGCAAGCCACCACUACGAACUCUCAAGAGGAGUGGGAGUGCGGGAGUCCAGAGCUGCCUCUGGGAAGUCUGCAGUAGUUGAGCAAAGGGGUCCUCACGUUCCUGAGAGCUGGGCAGGGGGGAUUUUGGAACCUGGGGCAGCCAAGAACGAGCAGCCAAGGGUACGGGAGAUUAGUUGUGCACAGAGCAGUGCUGGUCGGGCUUGGGGGUGGCUGGUGGGCACUGCGUGGGAAACCUUGGUUUGUAGUUUUCUUGGUUUGCGUUACUCCUGUUGGGUAGAAUUACCCUCCGCGCCUUUGUACAAGACACGGUGUCUCCUGGGGCAAGGAAGGAGCCAGGAUGGCCUGGGCUCUGAAGCUGCCUCUGGCCGACGAAGUGAUUGAAUCCGGGUUGGUGCAGGACUUUGAUGCUAGCCUGUCCGGGAUCGGCCAGGAACUGGGUGCUGGUGCCUAUAGCAUGAGUGAUGUCCUUGCAUUGCCCAUUUUUAAGCAAGAAGAGUCGAGUUUGCCUCCUGAUAAUGAGAAUAAAAUCCUGCCUUUUCAAUAUGUGCUUUGUGCUGCUACCUCUCCAGCAGUGAAACUCCAUGAUGAAACCCUAACGUAUCUCAAUCAAGGACAGUCUUAUGAAAUUCGAAUGCUAGACAAUAGGAAACUUGGAGAACUUCCAGAAAUUAAUGGCAAAUUGGUGAAGAGUAUAUUCCGUGUGGUGUUCCAUGACAGAAGGCUUCAGUACACUGAGCAUCAGCAGCUAGAGGGCUGGAGGUGGAACCGACCUGGAGACAGAAUUCUUGACAUAGAUAUCCCGAUGUCUGUGGGUAUAAUCGAUCCUAGGGCUAAUCCAACUCAACUAAAUACAGUGGAGUUCCUGUGGGACCCUGCAAAGAGGACAUCUGUGUUUAUUCAGGUGCACUGUAUUAGCACAGAGUUCACUAUGAGGAAACAUGGUGGAGAAAAGGGGGUGCCAUUCCGAGUACAAAUAGAUACCUUCAAGGAGAAUGAAAACGGGGAAUAUACUGAGCACUUACACUCGGCCAGCUGCCAGAUCAAAGUUUUCAAGCCCAAAGGUGCAGACAGAAAGCAAAAAACGGAUAGGGAAAAAAUGGAGAAACGAACACCUCAUGAAAAGGAGAAAUAUCAGCCUUCCUAUGAGACAACCAUACUCACAGAGUGUUCUCCAUGGCCCGAGAUCACGUAUGUCAAUAACUCCCCAUCACCUGGCUUCAACAGUUCCCAUAGCAGUUUUUCUCUUGGGGAAGGAAAUGGUUCACCAAACCACCAGCCAGAGCCACCCCCUCCAGUCACAGAUAACCUCUUACCAACAACCACACCUCAGGAAGCUCAGCAGUGGUUGCAUCGAAAUCGUUUUUCUACAUUCACAAGGCUUUUCACAAACUUCUCAGGGGCAGAUUUAUUGAAAUUAACUAGAGAUGAUGUGAUCCAAAUCUGUGGCCCUGCAGAUGGAAUCAGACUUUUUAAUGCAUUAAAAGGCCGGAUGGUGCGUCCAAGGUUAACCAUUUAUGUUUGUCAGGAAUCACUGCAGUUGAGGGAGCAGCAACAACAGCAGCAGCAACAGCAGCAGAAGCAUGAGGAUGGAGACUCAAAUGGUACUUUCUUCGUUUACCAUGCUAUCUAUCUAGAAGAACUAACAGCUGUUGAAUUGACAGAAAAAAUUGCUCAGCUUUUCAGCAUUUCCCCUUGCCAGAUCAGCCAGAUUUACAAGCAGGGGCCAACAGGAAUUCAUGUGCUCAUCAGUGAUGAGAUGAUACAGAACUUUCAGGAAGAAGCAUGUUUUAUUCUGGACACAAUGAAAGCAGAAACCAAUGAUAGCUAUCAUAUCAUACUGAAGUAGGAGUGCGGCGUUUCGUGCCCAGUGGCUGCUCCUUCCUUCACCUCUGAAAACGGCCCUCUUGAAGGGGGAUAUGAAUGGAGAUUUGAAGGUCUGCAAGAACCUGACUCGUCUGACUGUGUGUGGAGGAGUCCAGGCCAUGGAGGCAGAAUCCUGGCCCUCUGUGUUGGCCCAAGCUCUUGUGGUACACACAGAUUACUGCCCAAUAUGCAGUUCUGCAGCUGUUUUAGUUAAAUUUCUGGACCUUGUUGUUGUUAAAUAUCAGUAGAAACUCUACAUAAUUUAGAGUGUAUGUAGGGCAUAAUGAUGAUGGGAAUUGUGUGAUGUUUAACAGGAAGAUCUUAAAUUUUGUGAUAUGGAGCCCUGUAAUUUUUUUCUUAUAUAAAAAUGGGUAUCUAUAUUCAUAAGACUAGGUCUUCAAUCUCUUUGUACUGGUCUCAAAUGUACUGGUAUCUCUGCUUUUUGCCACAGUUUGUCCCUGAAAACUUUAUCAGUGAGGAGAAAUACAGAAUUUUCCUUUUGGUUCCCCUGUAAUACCACAACUAAUAGUAUUUUCAGCUAACAUUUAUUGACCAGGCAGUGUGAUAAAUUUUUUGAAUGACCAUCUUGUUUAACCCCCUAAUCACACUAUCUGAAGUAGGUGCUAUAGUGACCCCCAACCGAAGAUGAGGAAAUGGAGACACACAGUGGCUAAGUAGCUUGCUAGGUGCCAGGAGCUGGCAGGCAGUGAUGCUGAAAUCCAAACCAGGCAAUCUGGCCCUCCUUAUUCACCCUCUCAUACCACCAGUGCUACCCAUUAUAACCUGUGUUCACUUCGCUUAUUACUGUGGCCCUUCUGGUGACUACAACAUAACACUGAGUAUGAACUGAGGAAUUAACCACUGAAAGAGACAAAGCACACCUAAAUAAUGAUGAACAAAUCAAGACCUACAAGAAAUGAACACAUAGAUGCUUUUUAAGUGUCAUUAGUUAUCGGAAUCAAAGAAUUUGAGGUGGUGACAACUGGGGAUUAUCUGUAACUCCCCAAAUUUACUGUUCUUGAAUGACAUUCUCAAACUAUUUAUUAAUGAGUUAGUCUCAUCCCUGCUUUCUGUUUCCUCUCUCUGCAUCUUCUCUUGGCAUAGGAAGUUAUUUUACUCAUGCUAUGUUUUUUAAUAGAAGCUUUACAAAAAAAGAUGCAUUCCCUUCCUGUUCACACUCUUACCAUGUUUUUGUUCUUCCUUAAGAAUGAUUGUGUGUGUGUGUGUGUGUGUGUGUAAGUGUGUAAGUGUAACAUCAUGGGUUUUCUUUCUUCACUUGUAAAGUUUUAUCUAGAAAUACUUUUACAGGUUAUGUUGAGGUACACAAAGAUAAUGUUCUAAGAUUGUGUAUUGGAUUUGGAUUUGUGUGUGUGUGUGUGUGUGUGUGUGUUUAAAGCAUUUGAUAAGGUUUAAAUGUUUUUUAUACAGAGAUUUUUGUUCAUUAAACUCAAUCUGCAUCAUGGUCUAAUUUCUCUUGGUUUGAAACAAAUUGAAAACUUUGAAACCAAAAAAUUAAGUCAAUGACUUGUUUAAAACUGACCUGAGCAACUUGUUAUAUUACACCAAAA